AGUCUGAGGUUCCUGCUUUAAUGACCGGGGUAGUUUGAGCCAUUUCUGCGUCUUGCAGGACAUUUUGAACGAACCCCCUUUGCUUGAGGCUCGCAACCACCCGAUGAUCGAUGAUCGUCUCAGGGGAAAAGAAGCCUUGGCGAAGAGCAGAGGUUUAGAGGUGCGAGGGCGGGGAGGGUGUUUAUUGUUCCCGUCAGCGGAGCCUUCUGGCGUCGGGGGGCUUUGCUCGCCUCCCGGGGGGUGGGAUUGGGGUGGCCUUGUGUGCCCUGCUCUGAGGGUUUCCAGGACUUUGACCUCGCUCAGUCCGCCUCCCUACGUAUGCAGUGUGUACACUCUUUCUCGCAGUGUGAUGUGGAAUGUUAAUGUCUCUGUACUUCCCAUUGCUGUUCUUUAAAAUGGUGCUUAUAGGGUCAUCCUAAUAGAAUUGUUUUGCGAAUUGAAAGAGAUAAUACAAAUGAAAGCCUUAAAGUUGUCCCUGUCACUUGGUGAGUGGUCUCUUGUUGCCUGAUAUUUUAAAACGUUUGAUAUCAUUUCAAAGCUAUAGAAAAAUUGCAAAAACAGUAUAAGAAAUUCUCAUAUACCCUUUACCCAAAUUUGCCAAGUGUUUACAUUUUUCCUGUUUGCUUUGUUGAUGACCAUCAACCAAAUACCACCAGGAACAUACCUGUAACCAGAGACAGCUGAUUGGUAGCUUUCUGCAGCAAGGAAGCCCACAUACCACGGCACAAUUCUGCUUUCCCUGGAACUGUGUCAUUCAGGACUCUGCAAAUUCCCUAAAGUAGGAGGAAAAAUGACCAUGUCCAAGGAGGCAGUGACCUUCAAGGAUGUGGCAGUGGUCUUCACUGAGGAGGAGCUGGGGCUGCUGGACCUUGCCCAGAGGAAGCUGUAUCGAGAUGUGAUGCUGGAGAACUUCAGGAACCUGCUGUCAGUGGGGCAUCAACCAUUCCACCGAGAUACUUUCCACUUUCUAAGGGAGGAAAAGUUUUGGAUGAUGGAUAUAGCAACCCAAAGGGAAGGGAAUUCAGGAGGCAAGAUCCAACCUGAGAUGAAGACUUUUCCAGAAGCAGGACCACAUGAAGGGUGGUCCUGCCAGCAGAUCUGGGAAGAAAUUGCAAGUGAUUUAACCAGGCCUCAAGACUCUACCAUAAAGAGCUCUCAGUUCUUUGAACAGGGUGAUGCCCACUCCCAGGUUGAGGAAGGACUAUCUAUAAUGCACACAGGACAGAAACCUUCCAAUUGUGGGAAGUGUAAACAAUCCUUCAGUGAUAUGUCCAUCUUUGAUCUUCCUCAGCAAAUACGCUCAGCAGAGAAGUCUCAUUCCUGUGAUGAGUGUGGAAAAAGCUUCUGUUACAUCUCAGCGCUUCAUAUUCAUCAGAGAGUCCACCUGGGAGAGAAACUCUUUAAGUGUGACGUGUGUGGUAAGGAAUUCAGUCAGAGUUUACAUCUGCAAACUCAUCAGAGAGUCCAUACUGGAGAGAAACCUUUCAAAUGUGAACAAUGUGGGAGAGGCUUCAGAUGUAGAUCAGCACUUACAGUUCAUUGCAAAUUACACAUGGGAGAGAAACAUUAUAAUUGUGAGGCAUGUGGGAGGGCCUUCAUUCAUGAUUUCCAGCUUCAGAAACAUCAGAGAAUUCACACAGGGGAGAAGCCAUUCAAAUGUGAGAUAUGUAGUGUGAGCUUCCGUCUUAGGUCAAGUCUUAAUAGGCAUUGUGUGGUCCACACAGGAAAGAAACCAAACAGCACUGGGGAAUAUGGAAAAGGCUUCAUUCGUAGGCUGGAUUUGUGUAAGCAUCAGACGAUCCACACAGGAGAGAAACCAUAUAAUUGUAAAGAAUGUGGGAAGAGCUUCAGACGGUCCUCCUAUCUUUUGAUCCAUCAGCGAGUCCACACUGGAGAAAAGCCAUACAAAUGUGACAAGUGUGGGAAGAGCUACAUUACUAAGUCAGGUCUUGACUUGCACCAUAGAGCCCACACAGGAGAGAGACCUUAUAACUGUGAUGACUGUGGGAAGAGCUUUAGACAGGCCUCAAGUAUUUUGAAUCAUAAGAGACUCCAUUGCCGAAAAAAACCAUUCAAAUGUGAGGAUUGUGGAAAGAAGCUUGUAUACCGGUCAUACCGUAAAGACCAACAAAAAAACCACAGUGGAGAAAAUCCAUCCAAAUGUGAAGACUGUGGGAAGCGCUACAAGAGGCGCUUGAAUCUUGAUAUAAUUUUAUCAUUAUUUUUAAAUGACACGUAAGUGUUGUACAUAUUUAUGGGGUACAGUGUGAUAUUUAAAUAUAUGUAUAUGAUGUAUAAUGAUCAAAUCAGUGUAAUUAGCACAUUUAUCACCUCAAUUAUCUCUUUUUUGUGUUGAGAAAAUUAAAAAUUCAUUGUUCCAGCAGUUUGAAAAUAAAUUGUUGUCGAUGAUAGUCACCUUUAGUGCUGCAGAACAGCAGAACUUCUUCCUCUUAUCUACCUGUACUUUUGCAUCCAUUAGCCAACCUUUGGCCAUCCCACCUAUCCCUUACCCUUCCCUGCCUCUAGAGCCACUGUUCUCACUACUUCUAAGAAAUCAGCUUUUUAAGCUUCCCCAUGUGAUUGAGGACAGUUUGAAGUUAGUGUUUCAGCCAUAGCUCAGCAUACCCCAGUGGUCGUGGGACUGUCAGAGCAGAGAAUGCUGCAGGGUUUCUAACAGAAGUUUGACAAUUAGUUAUUAUUCAGGAGACAGGUCUUAGUAUAAGAGUUUGUUCACACACUUUCAAAACACUAAUGAUGAACAUGUCAAAAUUGAUGACCACUAGAAUGUCAGCCACAUGUGUCUUUGUAUUUUUGCUGCAUCCUUACAUUGCUUGAGUCUGGAAGAUUGAGGCUGCACUGACCUAUGGUAGUGCUACUGCACUCCAGCCAGGGCAACAGAGUGAGACCCUGUCUCCAAAAAAAAAAAUUAAAUAAAUACCUUUCUUUGUUUCUAGACAAGCA